CUCCCCCUCGCAUCCCCGGCCCCGCGCGCGCCCAGCAGAAGCGGGUCUGUGUGUGCGUGCGUGCGAGUGAGUGAGUGUGUGCAUAUUUUUUUCUCUCUUUUCUUUCUCUCUCACUGUUUUUUCCUCUCUCUCUCUCUCCCUCUCUCUCUCUUUUUUUUUUUUUUUUUUUUGCAAAGAAACAGCAGCGCCGCCGCCGCUCCGCCGAGGCGCUGCGCCCCCCGGGGGGGGAGGCGGAGGAGGCGGGCAGCGGCGGAGGGAGGGGAGCCGGGGAGGGGGGCGCCGCGCUGGGAGGGAGGCAGCGCGCACGGUGCAGCCGGGCCGGGCGGGAGGCAUGGCGGGGCCCCCGGCCCUACCCCCGCCGGAGACGGCGGCGGCCGCCACCACGGCGGCCGCCGCCUCGUCGUCCGCCGCUUCCCCGCACUACCAAGAGUGGAUCCUGGACACCAUCGACUCGCUGCGCUCGCGCAAGGCGCGGCCGGACCUGGAGCGCAUCUGCCGGAUGGUGCGGCGGCGGCACGGCCCGGAGCCGGAGCGCACGCGCGCCGAGCUCGAGAAACUGAUCCAGCAGCGCGCCGUGCUCCGGGUCAGCUACAAGGGGAGCAUCUCGUACCGCAACGCGGCGCGCGUCCAGCCGCCCCGGCGCGGAGCCACCCCGCCGGCCCCGCCGGCGCCGCCACAGCAGCAGCAGCCGCCGCCGCCGCAGCCACAGCCGCCGCCGGAGGGGGGCGCGGUGCGGGCCGGCGGCGCGGCGCGGCCCGUGAGCCUGCGGGAAGUCGUGCGCUACCUCGGGGGCAGCGGCGGCGCCGGCGGUCGCCUAACCCGCGGCCGCGUGCAGGGGCUGCUGGAGGAGGAGGCGGCGGCUCGAGGCCGUCUGGAGCGCACCCGUCUCGGAGCGCUUGCGCUGCCCCGCGGGGACAGGCCCGGACGGGCGCCGCCGGCCGCCAGCGCCCGCCCGUCUCGCAGCAAGAGAGGUGGAGAAGAGCGAGUACUUGAGAAAGAAGAGGAAGAAGAUGAUGAUGAAGAUGAAGAUGAAGAAGAUGAUGUGUCAGAGGGCUCUGAAGUGCCCGAGAGUGACCGUCCUGCAGGUGCCCAGCACCACCAGCUUAACGGCGAGCGGGGACCUCAGAGUGCCAAGGAGAGGGUCAAGGAGUGGACCCCCUGCGGACCGCACCAGGGCCAGGAUGAAGGGCGGGGGCCAGCCCCGGGCAGCGGCACCCGCCAGGUGUUCUCCAUGGCAGCCAUGAACAAGGAAGGGGGAACAGCUUCUGUUGCCACCGGGCCAGACUCCCCGUCCCCCGUGCCUUUGCCCCCAGGCAAACCAGCCCUACCUGGGGCCGACGGGACCCCCUUUGGCUGUCCUCCCGGGCGCAAAGAGAAGCCAUCUGAUCCCGUCGAGUGGACCGUGAUGGAUGUCGUCGAAUAUUUUACUGAGGCUGGAUUCCCGGAGCAGGCGACAGCUUUCCAAGAGCAGGAAAUUGAUGGCAAAUCUUUGCUGCUCAUGCAGCGCACAGAUGUGCUCACCGGCCUGUCCAUCCGCCUCGGGCCAGCCCUGAAAAUCUACGAGCACCACAUCAAGGUGCUUCAGCAAGGCCACUUUGAGGAUGAUGACCCCGAUGGCUUCUUAGGCUGAGCGCCCAGCCUCACCCCUGCCCCAGCCCAUUCCGGCCCCCAUCUCACCCAAGAUCCCCCAGAGUCCAGGAGCUGGACGGGGACACCCUCAGCCCUCAUAACAGAUUCCAAGGAGAGGGCACCCUCUUGUCCUUAUCUUUGCCCCUUGUGUCUGUCUCACACACAUCUGCUCCUCAGCACGUCGGUGUGGGGAGGGGAUUGCUCCUUAAACCCCAGGUGGCUGACCCUCCCCACCCAGUCCAGGACAUUUUAGGAAAAAAAAAAUGAAAUGUGGGGGGCUUCUCAUCUCCCCAAGAUCCUCUUCCGUUCAGCCAGAUGUUUCCUGUAUAAAUGUUUGGAUCUGCCUGUUUAUUUUGGUGGGUGGUCUUUCCUCCCUCCCCUACCACCCAUGCCCCCCUUCUCAGUCUGCCCCUGGCCUCCAGCCCCUAGGGGACUAGCUGGGUUGGGGUUCCUCGGGCCUUUUCUCUCCUCCCUCUUUUCUUUCUGUUGAUUGUCGCUCCAGCUGGCUGUAUUGCUUUUUAAUAUUGCACCGAAGGUUUUUUAAAUAAAAUUUUAAAAAAAGAAAAA